CUCCCGCAGGAGCGGACAGCCGGGAUCUCGGUGUGAGGUCGGGAUCGGAUGAGCCGUGUGGUUGGGGAUGUUCCCAGGUGUGCCUGGAUUUGGGCUCCAGUUGCAGCAUGGGGCCUUUCCCUCAUCAGGGAGCCCGUGGCCAGUGCUAGAUUUUCCAUAGCCCUCUGCAGCUGCCCACGUGUUGUUGUGGGAGAGGUGAUGGCGCCCACAGCACUCCUGUGUGCCCCAGCCCAUGCCAUCCUUCCAGUAACUGGAGGGUGGUGGGUGGGGCCGCGGCCCCAACCAGAGGCAGCUUCCUUUUAGUGUCAGAGCUCGAAGCUCUUCAUCUAACAGGGGCUUCUUACGUGAUGUGGCCGAGCGUUGGCUGUGGCCCUCCUGGAGACAUCAGGCUGGGAAGCCAGAGAGGGAUAGGGCCCUGGCCGUGGCUGUGCGUUUGCCCCGGGGCAGUGACAGGGCAGAUGCUGCUCCCUUGGCCACGCACAGGAGAGGGGAAGGUGGGCAUUGGGAAGUGGCGCAUCCCCCCUCCCCAGGCUGAUGCUGGCCAACUGAUGCUGCUUCUCAUAAUGCUGUUUCCUGUCUCGUGUCCGCCCUCUGCGUCCUUGCCGGUGGCAGCCUACUGGAGACAGGGAGCCCACACAGAAUCCUGACCUCACCAGAAAUGGGGCCCCAGGCACUUGGUGGGCAGGUUUGGCUGUGACUGGAGCUGGUGGUGAGGGACAUAGCCAUCCCAAGGCUAGGCCGGGCUUCCAGUCCUUCCUCAGGGACUUGUUUAUGGUGCCUGAGGGCUCCUUCCUGGUCCUGAGAUGAUGCUGUGGCCCCGCCUGGGCAGCUGCCCCAGCCCUGUUCCUGCCAACCCUGGGCUUUGGUGAUGCAGCACCUCUUGCACCCCGGCCUCCUGGCCCACUCCACCCCCUCACCCUGCUCCGUCUGUGCUGUGGCCCAGUCCUCUUAAAAGGAUUGAACACCUCCGGGUGGGAUGAGAACCUGUCCGUUCACUGUCACCAGGUGUCUCUCAGGCAUACCCAGGUGUCCUCACGUGUCUCUCGGGUGUCCUCAGGUGUCUCCCAGGCAUCCUCACGUGUCCCCAGGUGUCCCCAAGUAUCUCUCAGGCAUCCCCAGGUGUCCUCACGUGUCUCUCAGGUGUCCUCAGGUAUCUCUCACAUGUCCCCACGUGUCUCUCAGGGUGUCUCUCAGGUGUCCUCAGGUGUCUCUCAGGGUGUCUCUCACGUGUCCUCAGGUGUCUCUCAGGGUAUCUCUCACGUGUCCUCAGGUGUCUCUCAGGGUAUCUCUCACAUGUCCUCAGGUGUGUCUCAGGGUAUCUCUCACAUGUCUUCAGGUGUCUCUCAGGGUGUCUCUCACAUGUCCUCAGGUGUCUCUCAGGGUAUCUCUCACAUGUCCUCAGGUGUCUCUCAGGGUAUCUCUCACAUGUCCUCACGUGUCUCUCAGGUGUCUCUCAGGAUAUCUCUCACAUGUCCUCAGGUGUCUCUCAGGGUAUCUCUCACAUGUCCUCAGGUGUUUCUCAGGUGUCUCUCACGUGUCCUCAGGUGUUUCUCAGGUGUCUCUCACGUGUCCUCAGGUGUUUCUCAGGUGUCUCUCACGUGUCCUCCGGUGUCUCUCACUUGUCCUCAGGUGUUUCUCAGGUGUCUCUCACAUGUCCCCAGGUGUCUCUCAGGGUAUCUCUCACAUGUCCUCAGGUGUCUCUCACGUGUCCUCAGGUGUCUCUCACGUGUCCUCAGGUGUUUCUCAGGUGUCUCUCACGUGUCCUCAGGUGUCUCUCACGUGUCCUCAGGUGUUUCUCAGGUGUCUCUCACGUGUCUUCAGGCGUCUCUCACGUGUCCUCAGGCGUCUCUCACGUGUCCUCAGGCGUCUCUCACGUGUCCUCAGGCGUCUCUCACGUGUCCUCAGGUGUCUCUCAGGCGUCUCUCACAUGUCUUCAGGCGUCUCUCACGUGUCCUCAGGCGUCUCUCACGUGUCCUCAGGCGUCUCUCACGUGUCCUCAGGCGUCUCUCACGUGUCCUCAGGUGUCUCACGCGUCCUCAGGUGUCUCACGCGUCCUCAGGUGUCUCUCACGCGUCCUCAGGUGUCUCUCACGCGUCCUCAGGUGUCUCUCACAUGUCCUCAGGUGUCUCUCACGUGUCCUCAGGUGUUUCUCAGGCGUCUCUCACGUGUCCUCAGGCGUCUCUCACGUGUCCUCAGGUGUCUCUCACGUGUCCUCAGGUGUCUCUCACGUGUCCUCAGGUGUCUCUCACGCGUCCUCAGGUGUCUCUCACAUGUCCUCAGGUGUCUCUCACGUGUCCUCAGGUGUUUCUCAGGUGUCUCUCACGUGUCCUCAGGUGUCUCUCACGUGUCCUCAGGUGUCUCUCAGGUGUCCCCAGGUGUCUCUCAUGGAUCCCCAGGCAUCCUCAGGUGUCCCUGGCCCUGUGGAGAGCUCUCUGUACUGAGCUGUUUUUUGUUGUCUAGGGCAUCUCCCUUUGGUCUAAUCAUGUUUUCUUCAGAGAACAUGACCACAUACCAGGGAUAUUUUGGUCAUUUUUGCACUUUAGUCUUUAUUUUAUAUGCAUUCCUGCUAUUUCCGUUUAUUUAAAUAUGCUUGAAAUUCUCUGGAUUCUUUAACAGAUGUUAGGAUAUGAGUUUUAAGAGAGAGUGGCUUGUGGGUCACAGCCUUGAGGAUCUGAGCAGGAUUGCCUUCCCCGCGCUCCCUUCCCCGCGUCCCACUUCCCUGCGCCCCGCUUCCCCGCAGCCCCCCUCCCCGUGUGUGCUCCCACACAGCUGUCCUGAUUGAGCGGUUCCAGAUCCCAGGCAGCUUUUGUGGCCCCGUUUCCUGCCUGUGGAAGGUGACAAAAAACUUGCUCUGCAGAAGUUUUGUGGCCAUUGAAAGUAGCGGUUUGUGGAAGCCCUACCACGUCAUACGGCUUUUCAACCACGUUGCACAGCAGAUCACGGCUUUUCAGUAAAUGCCAUUUUGAUAAAAGCUAAAAAUUCAGUUUUUGUUUUGCUUGAUAAUUAGAUUAUAGGUUUGCUUAUAAGUUGACUAGGAAUUCUAAGUUUGAUUUUAUAGGUGCUGUGUGUCAUAGCAGAGUUUGUCUGGGUGAAUAAUUGUAGCACCACUUUCGUCUUUACUGCCGGUGUGAAUACACUGGGGGGAAACGAAUGAGAAGAUUAUCUUAUUGAUGUGCUUUAAACUUCGUCACUGAAAGUCAAGUUCCUGAUUUAAAUUCAGCUGUUCGGGUGGAGUUUGUCAUUGCUGUUUUGUGCUUUGCAAAAUCCCAGUGAUGGGAAUUAAAGCUGACAAAGGGCAAAUGUUUCUUAAACCUUUUUAUAUACCAGAGGUUUACAAAAAACUGGACUGGCUCAUUCUGACACGAGGGGUGGGGCUCAGUCCGGGCAUGUGAGUGAAAGCGGUGGGGAGGUCCUUAGGUCUCUGACCUGCACCAGUCAGCAGGCGCAGGGCUUGUCAAGGUCAGGGUCUUUUGAGGUGCGGAUGCUUGUGAAGCCUGUGGUGCUGCAGAGCUCAGCACGCGCACAGGAACGUGUGCGGGACAGAGGACAUAUGUGCUCAGCCGGCAGGAGCAGCGGCCUGUGUGAGCCCCUGGGGAGAAGCAGCCCCCCACCCAGGCCUGUGUCCCAGAAGUCGGCAUCUGUGGUCGCAGUGGCCUUUCCUUUGCAGCUGCGCCACUGGCCCUGUCUCUCUGGACACCGCGGUUAACCUUGGUCCAUCUCUAGGAUUCUGUGUCUGAGUGGGGUCACACUACACGGAGACAUCGUAAUCUCAGUUUUUAGAGUGUGUGAAAUUAAGGUGCAAAAAGUGUGCACUUAGGGCAGAAGGGAUGCCUUAAAUCAGGAGUCCCCAACCCCUGGGCCUGUUAGGAAGCUGGCCGCACAGCCGCCUGAGCCCUGCCUCCUGUCAGAUCCCAGCAUUAGGUUCUCAGGAGCGCAAACCCCACUGUGAACGGCACAUGCAGGAUCUAGGUGGCACUCCGUAUGAGAAUCGAAUGCCUGAUGAUCUGAGGUGGGACAGUUUCUUCCCGAAACUACCCCCGACUCCGGUCUGUGGAAAAACUGUCUUCCACAAAACUGGUCCCUGAUACCAAAAAGGUGGGGGAUCGCUGCUUUAAACACCAAGGCUCACUGUGCAGCCAGUGAGGAGGGGAGCUCCUGGGGGAGGAGGGUUGGUCUCGGGCAAGGUGGACCUCCGGCAGGUCCUCUACUGUGGGAUGCUUCCACCUGGAGCUGUUUUCUAACGACUGCUGGCGUGGAAGCUGCAAAAGCUUUAGAGUCGAAAGACUGUGUCUGAAGCCGUGUAAAGACUGUCUGGAGCCGUGUAAAGACUGUGUCUGAAGCUGUGUAAAGACUAUGUCUGGAGCCGUGUAAAGACUGUGUCUGAAGCCGUGUAAAGACUGUGUCUGAAGCCGUGUAAAGACUGUCUGGAGCCGUGUAAAGACUGUCUGGAGCCGUGUAGAGACUGUGUCUGAAGCCGUGUAAAGACUGUGUCUGGAGCCGUGUAAAGACUGUGUCUGGAGCCAUGUAGACUGUGUCUGAAGCCAUGUCAUUUACUUUCUCUGAAGCGCAGCUUGGAUUCCAGCCGUGAGCACAGUAGGAAGGGAGACCCCUUAUGACCUGUGGGGCCUGGGUCACCUCCCCUGCUCCCCAGCGAGAGGCGGGUGAGGGAGUCGUGAGGGCGGAGCCCAUCCUCCAGAGAAGCCGCUGUUAAAUCUAAGGGGUGGGUGUCCCUGGCGCCUUUCAGCCCCUGCCUGCCUCCUGCUCCCAGAGGCUCCUGGAUCUCCUGGAAAGCCCUGGUUGGAGUGGGACCCACAGCCUCCCAGCUUUGGGCAGUACCCCUCAUUGUGCUGUGACCACUUCUCCCUUCCAGGGUCUCUGCCCACCACUCCAGCUAGCGUGGCCACUGCUUCCAAUACCUCCUUUUUUUCCCUAGGGGCCCAGCUCUGAACUAUCCUUCCCGGCACUGUCCCAUCCACCCUUUGGCACCUCCUUGGUUCCUGUUUUCCCUGCGCUUCUGCCCACACACGCCCUCCAGGGCUUCAGUGUGUUGCCGUGCCUCCUCUGGCUGUUGAGUGUGGCUCCUGGUGUAGGGAAGUGAGGCCGGGGGCCUGCUCCAUGUCUGUUGAAUGGGAGACUGGAAGGCGUCCUGUGGCACAGGCGGCCGGCCCGAGUUCACCGGCUUCCUGUGCACCAGGAAGGAAACGCACACACCUGUGCCAGGUCCGGGAGCAAAGCCUCUGUCUCGUUCCUGGGAGGGCUGGCUCCAGGCCGCCCCUGUGAUGCUGACUCAGCUCACAGGGCUGGUGAGCAGCAGGUGAUGGGUGAGGAGCAGGGACAGUGCUGCGGAGACACAGUGAGGGGAGCUGCCACGCAGGGCACGCAGAGGAAGGUGCAGGCACCCUUGCCCAGCACUGCAUGGGCCGGAUGCCGCGGGGCCUUCCGCAGGGAGCAGUUAAAGCAGGAGAGUAAGGAGAGCUUCCUGUAAGACCUGGCCUCCGUAAACAACGCAUUCCCAGUGCACUGGUGGCUCGUUCUCAGGGUGCCCCUGGGUGCUGAGUCCUGUCUUCCAGGAAAGGUUGUUGGUGAGCACCAUUGAGCACCUGGUGUGUACCUGCCUCUGGCUUUCUCUUCUUCCCAACUUACAGUGGGUUUGACCUGUGAUUUUGACUUUAAGAUGGUCCAAAAGCAACAUGCAUUCAGUGGAAACUGCUUCCACUGCCCAUACGACCGUCCUAUUUUUCAUUUUGAGUGUGGUAUUCAGUGGGUCUCCUGGGAUACCCACACUUGACUAGAGUGGGCUUUGUGUGAGAUGCUUCUGCCCGACUGGGCUAACAUGCGUGAUCUGAGCACGUGUAAGGUAGGCUGGCUAAGCUGUGAUGUGUGGUAGGAGAGGUGGAUGACGUGCAUUUCGACUUAGGGUAUUUUCAGCUCAUGCGGGUUUAUCGGGAUGUUCCUUGUAAGUUCCUCGUUGUAAGUCAGUUCCUCGUUGUAAGUCCACUCUUUGUGAGUAGGUUUGCUCCUGCCUGGAGGACAGCGGCACGGUGACGGCAUCUGUUUUGGGGCCAAGAUCCAGUGCCUUGCGUGGUCCUGGGAUUCCUGGGGAAGGGAGUGGACCCAUGAGGUGGGUUAGAAUCGUGUGUGGGAUUCUCCAGCCCCCUGUACCUGUGCGUGUGGUAUGCGCGGAGCCAGCCAGCACUGCCUGGCGUGGAGCUGGCGGGUUCUCAGUCUGACAUCAACUCCCGGAGAAUGGCAUCUGCUGAACUCAACGUAGGAAGCCGUGCGGGGCCAGCGCGCUCUCAGGCAGCCUGAGUGGCAGGGUCCUUUUGUCAGCUGUUUGGAUCUCCCACGUGGCCCAGUGCCCCAGCAGCACACACACACACACACACACACACACGCGUAUUGAACAAAACAAGUUUCACAGGACAUUUAUCCACGCCCAGGAGAUUUAUCUUUUGUAUGGCUUCAUUUUGCAGAAAAUUCACUUGUUUGAUUUCAUGGCCUGGUGAUCCACAGAAGGCCGCACUCUGAUGAGUCUCUGAUCAUCGGAGAGAUGAGUGUCAAUGAAAAGAUCAGUCCUUGAAAUGUUUUUCUUCUCCGGAGCUGACAGGUGAUCUGGCCUAGGGAUAAUUGGAAAGUGUCCCCGUCAGCUGCUCCCAGGGCCACCGCAGGUGAUGCAUUUAUCCCCGUAAGAAGGGGAGCUGGGGGGGCCCAGCUUAGAGUAGCUCAGGGCAUCGGCCACAUGAAGCCCCCCCGCCAGCAUACAGGUGUCCAGCUCCAAUCCCUUUAACGGAAACUGCAUGUCCAUACAAGCAGUAUAAUCGCUGAGGCACUUUGAUUUGUGGUGAAUUGAAUGAUUUAACAUUUACUGAGAAAUAGUGUUUCCAGUUUAGAUAGAGUCGUGCCACAAGAUCUUUGAAAAGUCAGAGUUGUAUUUGCCUGUAUGAGGGUGUCCAGGUAUUCACACUCGAACAUUCAUUGUUGGAACUAAAGUGGUAAGACCUUGUCAAGAGUCAGACCAGCCAGCAUGUCCCUGAAGGGAGAGACAGUUGUUGACACCCUCAGGUGUGCUGUGGGGUGGGGCGGGUGGGUCAGUGUCCACACUGGCGUUGCCUCUGGUGGUUCCCCCCAGAGGGGCCCAGGUGUGUGAGCCCCAGGGGCGUGUGGAGCCCCUACCUUCCGCCCCCAGUGCUGGUGGCCCUCCCUCCUUGCCUGACGCCGUUGUGGGUGCAGGGGUUCCCCCAGACAGGGCCCCAGGGCACAGGGUUACCAGGUGAUGGCUGUCACCCUGCUGGGCUGGAGGAGCAGCUGCUGUCACCCUGCCUGUGCUUUUGUCUUUUGAGAGCUGUUUUUGGUUUGUUUCAGGCCUCUUUUUAGUACCACAGAAGGAUACAAUUUCAUCCUCAUCCAUAUCACUAAAAGGAAGUAAAAGGGUGAAGGGAAAAAUGGAAGCGUGCUCAAGUGCCCUGUGUGGAAUUCUGUGCCGCCCCCUUCAUUAAACUUGACCGUUAGCGCCU